AAUUGCUGCGCCUGGUGGCACCGUGGAAUGAGGGGAGGCCAGCCUUCUCGGUGCGGAAUCUCCUUGGCCCAGGCCUUCCCAGGCUGCCCGUCCCGCCGCGGCUCAGGGCGCCUCCCGGCUCCCUGCCGCCUCCCAGCCGGACGCGGACGUGCCUGCGCGGCUCUGGCGGCCGCGUCUGCCGCCCCGGCGCCCGCCCGGGUCCCAGGCCGACUAAUUAGGCCCGGCUACCUCCCGCGCCGCCCACUGCCCGCUCCAGGCCCGCUGCCCGCUCCAGGCCCGAGGUGAUGGCGGCUGUUCCUGCCGUUCUGGGGCCUGUGCCCCAGAGCUGGCCGCGUUUCUCGGGGCGGGAGCCAGCUCUGCUCGCCUGGCUUAACCCAGACGAGCCCAGGACGCCCUAUCCCUGAACCCCAUCGUGGCGUGCAGGUCUGAGUAGGCUCUGGGCCAUGCCGGGGUACCUGGCUUGGAGGCUCUCUUCAGUCUCGGGAGAGAUAUGCUUAUCCCAGGCGGAGCGGAGAAGGCUGGGGGAUGACUGAUAGGGGGAGUCGGGAGGGGAUGUUGAGCCCUGAGGUGUUGCACUGAGCACGGAUCCAGUUCCUCUUGGCUUUGCCACAAACACAGUGACCUUAUGUAGAGUCCUUAGCCUCGGUUUCCCCGUUUGUAAACCAUCAGCACCAGCCCAUUUUCUCCUGAAUUUGGGAUUUAGGGAGCUGGGCUUUGUAUACCCCUCCCAGUCUCCUCUCUUGGGGGGUUGCUGAGGGGGUGGAGGUAAUGUCUGGACCUAGCAGGGCCUGCCUUACUGCCAUGAGCCCUGGAUGCCAGUGGCCAGCCUGCUCGCUGUGCUGAGGGCCAGGCAGGCCCUGGGCACUGAGGCACGUUGUUUGCUGAAACCAAAUUUCUGUGCUUGUGUUUUUCCAUAAUUAUAUUAGCAGGUGGGAUUUUUCCUCGGGGAAGCAGUGGGAGGGGGAGCGCCAUGGCAGUGUCCCCGCCCGCUCUAAGCGUGAGCUCACACUCAGCUCUGCCCGCCUGCCGUAAUGAUUUUUUAAUUAUGCAGCCAGUGCUCGGAAUUGCUAAUCCCCCUCCAGCCCUGCAUCCCCUCCUGCAACUCACACCCCAGCCCCUGGCUGAUGUCCCUAGAGUGGCGGUGCCCAGCCCCGUGCCCAUCACUGAGUGCUUGGGACAACCGCCAUAGCGGGAGAGAGGGUAGGUCAGGAAGGGCCGGAGGGGCGCCCCUCCGCCAUCUGCAAGUGACAAGACUUGUGGCUCUCUUUGUCUCCCACCCUACCCCUAGACCCAGCAUGGCUCACACCUGCCAGGACAGCUAUGGCUUUAAAUGAGUUUGGGGAGUGAUCGGUGCCCACACCAAGUGAUGUGGCCACACUCAUUUCAUGGACAUUAGCCUGUCUUCCCAGCCUUGUGUGACCCCAAGGACACAGGCACACAAGUACAAUUUUUGUCACACCCAUACUCACGCUUUACUUCCCUUCUACACACACACUCAGCCCCACAGCCAAGCUACACACACACACACAAUGGCAGGCUCUGCGUGCUUCUCACACAUGUAGCCUUACCUGAGGGCGGGGGCACCCUCAGGAGACCCCACUGCUGCCUCCUGUGCCCUGCAGUGGCCCUGCUCCCACUCCCUUGCCUCCAGACCCCCCAACCCCAUCCCCAUCCACCCUACUGGGAGGUGCUCCGAGGUCUUCUGGCUCCCGCCUCAUGGGGUGGCUGCCUGUGGCUGGGGCCAGCCUGAGCCUCCAUCGACCCUGGCCUGGGGGAGGUGCUGGGGGGGUUCUGCAGCACUGUGGCGGCGGCUCCUCUCCAGGCGCCCAGCUGUGGCAUCUGUCAAGGUCAGAUAGCGACUCCGGAACCAGCCGGCUCGGCCCCAUGGCCCCUCUCGCCUCAUUAUUUUUGUGUUCCGGGGCUGCGGCGACACCUCCCUCCCUCCUCCUCAGCCUCCCGCCUCUCGCCUGCCUCCCCCACGCCUCUGCAGGGAGGGCCUGCGGUCUGGGGGCUUUUGUUUUCCAGUUUUUUCCACGCUCAGGCCAGGCAGGCGGGUAGACACUGGCCAGAGCUGUUGGACCUUGAACAGCAGACAAGACAGGUGUCCCCCUUAGAGCUGGGACAGAUUCUCAGCUAGUGGAACCCUGGGUUGGUUUCUCAGAGGCACAAACUGAACCUGGAUGGAACCAGCCCCCACCACAGCCCAGGUGCACCUGUGGGCAGCUUCCUGUUUCCAUAGGGGCCCUAGCAGCUGGCACCAGUUCCUGUCUACACCAUCCCCGUCCCAGUAGGGCCCCAGACUCAUACAGCCCAGAGCUCCUGACACAACUCACAGUGCAUGCGGACAUACACACACUGGCAUUCAUGCGGCAAAGAUGUGUUGACACGUACAGACCAGAAGACUCCACAAACAUCCUCUCACCACGUAAACCACCCUAUUCGCACACACGUGCACUUGGACAUCCAUGUACAUUCACAGACUUGGGUCGCACACACAUGCCUCCACUUUACCCUCAGGGAGGUCACAGAGUCAAAGAUCUCCCCCAGCACUGCUACAUGAUCCCCAUAUAUGCUUUAAUGCUGUGGUCUGUAGAGGGCGACAUCUUGAGACUACACACUCAACCGGGCACAUUCACAGUCCACUGGACACACACACAGUUGUGCAGCACACCUCCCAGGUAGACACGCGAAAACACACUGUAUGCAUUGCUCUCGUCACCAUACACACUCCAGCCCCCUGAGCCCGCUCCCAGGUGCCCAGCAUCCUUGGGUAGUUAUGCCACCCGAGGGGCUUUUGUCCCCCGAAAUACUGGGAAGUGAGCUUGAGGCCUCAGCUUGCUGAGCCCUGUGUCCAGGGAGCCUCGGAGAGUGGGAAAUGGUUUGACAAGGACUGCCCGGCCCCUGCCCAACCUCACUGUGUACACCACUUUAGGCCCAAGAGCGCCAGGAUGGCGUGGGAUGGGGCGGGGGGUUCCAGGUGUGUCAUGAUGGGCUUGGUGGCUGCUGGCAGAGGCAGACUCUGGGGGGUGACCUCAGCUCUGUCUCUGGGUCCCUCCUCCCACCUCCAGCCCCUGAUUUGGGUGUGUAAAUGUUGGAGGAAUGGGGUGUGGGCAGACUCCAGGCCCCCAGGGUCUCUAGAGUGGCCCUGGCCAUCCCCUCUCUUCCUCCUCCAGCUGUGGACUGCUGUGACUGCCCCCGGGAGAGGAGCUAGAUGGAGGCUUAGCAGUGGCUGGGCCCCCACCCCCCAGGAAACUCAAAACCCUGGGCCAGCCGCGGGUGGCGGGUUGGGGCAGGCACAAAGAGGGCCUCUGUGCGGCCGGCUGGGCUGCCCACAGGAUUCUGGGGGAGGAGGCCGGAGCCGGUUUCCGUCCCGUUCUGCUUCCUGCGGAGGCUGCGGAAUGCCCGGAGCUCUGGCCCAGCCUGCCCCGUCUGGCCCACCCGCAGCCCCUUCCCCAUCUUUUCCAGGGCCUUGGGGUACAGCUGCAGACUUCUCUGCAACAGGGCCCUGAGAGCCACCCUCCAGGACCCAAGGGAAACCUAGGGGAUUUCCCCAAGCCGAGAGCUGAACUGGACCUCACCCUUUAGCUGAAGUCUUCCUUCCCUCCAUGUGCUGUGGAACCCUCAGCCAGGGUUGGAGCACCAGGCCCUGGAGUCACACAGACCUGGGUUUAAAUCCUGGCUCUGCCACUUACUGACCUUGUGACCUUAGGCAGGUGGCUUUAUGUCCCUGAGCCUCAGUUGCCUCAUCUGUAAAAUGAGGAUAAUAAUAAUUGUAGUAGAAUCCGGUGAGAAAAUGCAUGUGAAAUGCUUAGCACAGUGCCUGGUGGACAGUGAGUGUGCAUUAUUAGGACCUGCUGUUUAUUUUUUUUUAUUUAUUUGUUUGUUUGUUUAUUUAUUGUUUUGAGAUGGAGUUUUGCUCUUGUUGCCCAGGCUGGAGUGCAAUGGCGUGAUCUUGGCUCACUGCAACCUCUGCCUCCCAGGUUCAGGCAAUUCUCCUGCCUCAGCCUCCCGAGUAGCUGGGAUUACAGGCAUGCACCACCACGCUCGGCUAAUUUUUGUAUUAUUAGUAAAGACAGGGUUUCUCCAUGUUGGUCAGGCUGUUCUCGAACUCCCGACCUCAGGUGAUCCACCUGCCUCGGCUUCCCAAAGUGCUGGGAUUACAGGCGUGAGCCUGUACAGGCCAGGGCCUGCUGUUUAUUUUAAUGUCCUCUGGGGAACUUAAGAGUGGAAGGGACUGGAUGCUCCUUGCCACGAUAGGUCUCACCUCUUCUACGGUUCAGUCUCAGCCCUGCGUCCUGCUCAAAACCCUUCUCUCAAAUCAGUUUCCUAUCUGCAGAUCAUAUCAGUGACUGAUCUCGGCCUCUGGGGCCUUCCUCCUGAGGUCUGGAGGGUGGAGGGGAUCGCUGUCUGGAAUCCUUUUUUUCCCCUCUGUAUCUCUACCUCCUUCCCCAUGAUAUGCCCUGGGAUCGUGACUUCUGCAGUAGUUUGGGGUGAGAAGCAAGAGCCAUUCCUUUCCAUUUUACAAAUGGGAAACUGAGGCUUAGUGGCGGAAAGAGCUUGGUCAAAGUCACCAGUCAGGGAGGGACAGGGUGGAGCCACAAACCUAGGCCUCAGGCCUCCAGUUCCCUAGCCAGUCCUAGGCACAUAUGCCUCCCCCAACCCCAGACACACAAACACACCCCACACAGGAGCCCCAGAAGGACAGUGCGCCAUCUCUGAUUUCUUGACUCGUGCAUCCCUGGACUAGCCUUCCCUGGCUUGUCCCAUGGUGAGGCCCAUCAGUAGGGAGGUCCUGAGGGGGUACGUGGGCCUGAUUUCUGAUUGGUGUCAGCUCAGAGAUCACCACAUUGGGAAAUGUUUACUACAAGAUUCAGGGGAUCCCAGAUAGACAAGGCGUCAUUACACCUGCUUAAGCAAAUUGCCUGCUCUAAAUGGGGCAAUAAUAGGACUUCCUUCAGAGAUUGGGUAUGAGGAUAACAUGAGAUAAAGCAUGGACAGUGUGGCACAUAGGAAGAGCCCCAUACUUGUUAGCUAUGGUCCCAGGUGACAGAUGGGAAAACUGUCUCAGAGGCCAGUUUUUUCCCAAGGUCAAAAAAUGGGGAAGGGUCUUCCUGAACCUUUGACUCUUCCAGGAAAGGAACCUGGCCUGAGGGAGGUGCCUAUUGAGGAAAGGGCCUGUCUUUAUCAGAGGCAUCCCAGGCAUCUCAGUCCCUAGAGCCCCAGGUCAGAGCUUACUCCCUGCCCGGGGCCUCAGUGUUGCUGUGCAUGAAUGGGCUGAUCCCCUCCUCCAGCUGUUUUGGGGAGCACCGUAAAACAGAACAGAGCCUGGCUGGGUGCGGUGGCUCACGCCUGUAACCCCAGCACUUUGGGAGGCUGAGGUGGGUGGAUCACCUGAGGUCAGGAGUUCAAGACCAGCCUGACCAACAUGGUGAAACUCCAUCUCUACUAAAAAUACAAAAAUUAGCCAGGUGUGGUGGUGUGCGCCUGUAAUCCCAGCCACUCUGGAGGCUGAGGCAGGAGAAUUGCUUGAACCUGGGAGGCGGAGGUUGUGGUGAGCUGAGAUCGGGCCACGCACUCCAGCCUGGGUGACAGAGCAAGACUCUUGUCAAAAAAAAAAAAAAAAGAGAGAGAGAAAACAGAGCUCUACAUACUCCAGGUUUGCUCAAACCCUUUAGUCCUCAGGCCAAGGCAUGGUUGGCACCCACCCCAGCAGGAGGGGUGUAAGAGGGUCAGGGGUGUGGAGUCGGGGAUAUAGAAAUGCUGUCCCUUGUUCUGUCCUUGGCAGUCAGUCUUGGGGUGACUCUAGUGGGGUUGAGGCCAUGUCUCACCCCAGGCCACCCUCUGGGUGCUCGCAGUGGCCAGUGUGUGGGGGUAUGUGUGUCCAUCCAUAGCUGGAUGUGUGCCCUGUGCUCUCCGCCUGGGGCUGCGUUUCUCCCUGCCUCCAAGACCAGUCUCCCUGGGCUUGAGCAGGGCUUCUUUUUCCCUCUGGAAACUCCCCAGGCUGAAUCAUGGAAAUCAGAGACGGGACACCCUCCCUUCCACCCCAUUGCCCAGCUUGGUUCAACCACCAUAGCCUGUGGUCUGCUUUGCCCACCAUCAGCCUGUCUGCGUAUUUUGCCUCACUUGGAGGCAGGCCAAGGAGACCGGCCCACCAAGGUGGGGGGGAGGAGACAAGGGCCGGGAUGUCAAGUGCUGCAUGGAAGCGUGGAAAGUGGUGCAUUGAGCCAGGGUGUGCAGCUCUGCUGGGCCAGUGUUGGGGGUCCUGAAACGCAGCCUCUUCCACGAGCCUCCCUGGGCAGGCAGAAUGGCUGCAAGGCUGGUCAGCCAGCAAGGAAUGGCGGGGAUGGUGCCUUGGUCAAACCCUGCCCUUGGUAGUGGUGAUGGUUGCACAACUUUGUUGAUUUACUAAAAAUCAUUAAAUUAUAUGUAUACUUUAAUGUGGCAGAAUUUUAUAGUAUGUAAACUAUACCUCGAUAAAACUGUUUUUUAAAAAUCCUGCCAGCCAGGCGCAGUGGCUCACGCCUAUAAUCCCAGCAUUUUGGGAGGCCCAGGUGAGAGGAUUGCUUGAUCCUCAUAGGAAGACCUCAUCCCUACUAAAAAUUAAAAUAAUAAUAAUAAUAAAAAUUCUGCCCUUGGCCUCAAGGCCCUGCACAACUGGGACCCUGACAGCCUCAUAGACACACCUCACAUCUUCUUCCCCACCUGCUUAGGCUCUCUUUCAUGCCUUUGUCCCCUCUCAUUGCUUCUCCUUAUCCUUAACUCUCAAACUAGCAGUCCCUUCCUCCAGGAAGGCCUCAGAUAGCUCAUUGUGUCCCCUUCCGGCUCUUGUUUCACGCUGGUUCAUGUGACUGUGGGCCCAGCUCCUGUGCACUCCUGGAAGGCAGUGCUGGGGUCUGGGUCUGUGUGCUCUGCUGUCUCUCCGGUAUCAUAAGGUACAGGGCUGCUGUCGAGGUAGGUGCAGGGAAGAUGUGUGCAAAGGAAUAUCUAGAACAUCCAGCUGUGGGCCACCUGUGUACAUGUCUGUGUGCAGAUGGCACUAUGUCAUCCCAGGAUGUCCCCUCCUUCCCAGUGCUUUCUGGCCCGAGAGUUCAAGAUUGAACCCUGCGGGGGGUGAAGUGAGGCUCUUCUAGGGCUGAGGGUUGAAUAAGGGCACUGCCACCACCUCCAGUGACCUCACUGCCAGCUGGCAUUAUGAUGUCACUGGCUUAGCAUUCCAGGCCCUGGGCAUCUCCAAGUGCCCCAGGUGGGGGCACUCUCCUGGGGUCUGUGACAGCUUGCCCCCAACCACGGAGAGAGUGAAGACAUUUCCACCUGGACACCUGACCAUGUGCCUGCCCUGAGCAGCGAGGCCCACCAGGCAUCUCUGUUGUGGGCAGCAGGGCCAGGUCCUGGUCUGUGGACCCUCGGCAGUUGGCAGGCUCCCUCUGCAGUGGGGUCUGGGCCUCGGCCCCACCAUGUCGAGCCUCGGCGGUGGCUCCCAGGAUGCCGGCGGCAGUAGCAGCAGCAGCACCAAUGGCAGCGGUGGCAGUGGCAGCAGUGGCCCAAAGGCAGGAGCAGCAGACAAGAGUGCAGUGGUGGCUGCCGCCGCACCAGCCUCAGUGGCAGAUGACACACCACCCCCCGAGCGUCGGAACAAGAGCGGUAUCAUCAGUGAGCCCCUCAACAAGAGCCUGCGCCGCUCCCGCCCGCUCUCCCACUACUCUUCUUUUGGCAGCAGUGGUGGUAGUGGCGGUGGCAGCAUGAUGGGCGGAGAGUCUGCUGACAAGGCCACUGCGGCUGCAGCCGCUGCCUCCCUGUUGGCCAAUGGGCAUGACCUGGCGGCGGCCAUGGCGGUGGACAAAAGCAACCCUACCUCAAAGCACAAAAGUGGUGCUGUGGCCAGCCUGCUGAGCAAGGCAGAGCGGGCCACGGAGCUGGCAGCCGAGGGACAGCUGACGCUGCAGCAGUUUGCGCAGUCCACAGAGAUGCUGAAGCGCGUGGUGCAGGAGCAUCUCCCGCUGAUGAGCGAGGCGGGUGCUGGCCUGCCUGACAUGGAGGCUGUGGCAGGUGCCGAAGCCCUCAAUGGCCAGUCCGACUUCCCCUACCUGGGCGCUUUCCCCAUCAACCCAGGCCUCUUCAUUAUGACCCCGGCAGGUGUGUUCCUGGCCGAGAGCGCGCUGCACAUGGCGGGCCUGGCUGAGUACCCCAUGCAGGGAGAGCUGGCCUCUGCCAUCAGCUCCGGCAAGAAGAAGCGGAAACGCUGCGGCAUGUGCGCGCCCUGCCGGCGGCGCAUCAACUGCGAGCAGUGCAGCAGUUGUAGGAAUCGAAAGACUGGCCAUCAGAUUUGCAAAUUCAGAAAAUGUGAGGAACUCAAAAAGAAGCCUUCCGCUGCUCUGGAGAAGGUGAUGCUUCCGACGGGAGCCGCCUUCCGGUGGUUUCAGUGACGGCGGCGGAACCCAAAGCUGCCCUCUCCGUGCAAUGUCACUGCUCGUGUGGUCUCCAGCAAGGGAUUCGGGCGAAGACAAACGGAUGCACCCGUCUUUAGAACCAAAAAUAUUCUCUCACAGAUUUCAUUCCUGUUUUUAUAUAUAUAUUUUUUGUUGUCGUUUUAACAUCUCCACGUCCCUAGCAUAAAAAGAAAAAGAAAAAAAUUUAAACUGCUUUUUCGGAAGAACAACAACAAAAAAGAGGUAAAGACGAAUCUAUAAAGUACCGAGACUUCCUGGGCAAAGAAUGGACAAUCAGUUUCCUUCCUGUGUCGAUGUCGAUGUUGUCUGUGCAGGAGAUGCAGUUUUUGUGUAGAGAAUGUAAAUUUUCUGUAACCUUUUGAAAUCUAGUUACUAAUAAGCACUACUGUAAUUUAGCACAGUUUAACUCCACCCUCAUUUAAACUUCCUUUGAUUCUUUCCGACCAUGAAAUAGUGCAUAGUUUGCCUGGAGAAUCCACUCACGUUCAUAAAGAGAAUGUUGAUGGCGCCGUGUAGAAGCCGCUCUGUAUCCAUCCACGCGUGCAGAGCUGCCAGCAGGGAGCUCACAGAAGGGGAGGGAGCACCAGGCCAGCUGAGCUGCACCCACAGUCCCGAGACUGGGAUCCCCCACCCCAACAGUGAUUUUGGAAAAAAAAAUGAAAGUUCUGUUCGUUUAUCCAUUGCGAUCUGGGGAGCCCCAUCUCGAUAUUUCCAAUCCUGGCUACUUUUCUUAGAGAAAAUAAGUCCUUUUUUUCUGGCCUUGCUAAUGGCAACAGAAGAAAGGGCUUCUUUGCGUGGUCCCCUGCUGGUGGGGGUGGGUCCCCAGGGGGCCCCCUGCGGCCUGGGCCCCCCUGCCCACGGCCAGCUUCCUGCUGAUGAACAUGCUGUUUGUAUUGUUUUAGGAAACCAGGCUGUUUUGUGAAUAAAACGAAUGCAUGUUUGUGUCACGAA